GUUCUUGGACAUCAAAGCUGGGGCUUAGGCGCUGUGCUGGGGUCGCGGCGGCGCGGGCGCUGGGGGAGAGGAGUGUGGUCUUCAGCAUAGAGUGAGCUUCUAGUGACACGAGCUGGAGGGAAAGAGGAAGUGCAUCAGGACGGCUCGUCCAAUGGACAAGAAGGGCUGAACUGAUGGAAGGAAUGCUGUUAGCCUGAGACUCAGGAAGACAACUUCUGCAGGGUCACUCCCUGGCUUCUGGAGGAAAGAGAAGGAGGGCAGUGCUCCAGUGGUACAGAAGUGAGACAUAAUGGAAUCAGGCUUCACCUCCAAGGACACCUAUCUAAGCCAUUUUAACCCUCGGGAUUACCUAGAAAAAUAUUACAAGUUUGGUUCUAGGCACUCUGCAGAAAGCCAGAUUCUUAAGCACCUUCUGAAAAAUCUUUUCAAGAUAUUCUGCCUAGACGGUGUGAAGGGAGACCUGCUGAUUGACAUCGGCUCUGGCCCCACUAUCUAUCAGCUCCUCUCUGCUUGUGAAUCCUUUAAGGAGAUCGUCGUCACUGACUACUCAGACCAGAACCUGCAGGAGCUGGAGAAGUGGCUGAAGAAAGAGCCAGAGGCCUUUGACUGGUCCCCAGUGGUGACCUAUGUGUGUGAUCUUGAAGGGAACAGAGUCAAGGGUCCAGAGAAGGAGGAGAAGUUGAGACAGGCGGUCAAGCAGGUGCUGAAGUGUGAUGUGACUCAGAGCCAGCCACUGGGGGCCGUCCCCUUACCCCCGGCUGACUGCGUGCUCAGCACACUGUGUCUGGAUGCCGCCUGCCCAGACCUCCCCACCUACUGCAGGGCGCUCAGGAACCUCGGCAGCCUACUGAAGCCAGGGGGCUUCCUGGUGAUCAUGGAUGCGCUCAAGAGCAGCUACUACAUGAUUGGUGAGCAGAAGUUCUCCAGCCUCCCCCUGGGCCGGGAGGCAGUAGAGGCUGCUGUGAAAGAGGCUGGCUACACAAUCGAAUGGUUUGAGGUGAUCUCGCAAAGUUAUUCUUCCACCAUGGCCAACAACGAAGGACUUUUCUCCCUGGUGGCGAGGAAGCUGAGCAGACCCCUGUGAUGCCUGUGACCUCAAUUAAAGCAAUUCCUUUGACCUGUCCAGUUGACUUUAGUCCUUGUUUCUAACUGCCAAGUCAUGUGCUGAGUAGAGGCUCAGUGGUUGGGGCCCAAUGGUUCAUCUAGGACGGGACUAGAGAGGUCAGUCUACAAGCAAUCCAUUGACCACUUACUUGGUGCUGCACACAAAUGUUGGUGCUAUGGGACCCAAAGAUGAGCAAUUAGUAUUCCAGUCUUCAUUGCCUGUGCUUACAAAAGAAGACCUCACUUCCCUAAACAUCUAGUUAUGGCGGCUCAAGCCCGUACCUGCCUACAGAGAAGUGUCUGCAGUUACUCACUAUUAGUUUCCUAAGGGGGCACUGCUGGCUCCUUCUCUCCCAGGAAUGGGCUUCUCCUAUUCUUUAACUCUUGCCUUCUCCCUGGAGAGGCUACCAAACCCUGGCCUCUGCCGCUGUUCAGGCUGCCAUGUGGGUAUAGCUGUUUGCUAGACUCCACUCUGGCCUCAGGGGCCAGAGAACAGCUGUCCAGCAUUUCUGUUCAUCCCAGCAAUCCAAAAAAAAAUUUUUUUAAGCUACAAAGAUCACUCCAUUUUCAAAUUCAGACUCUGCCACUUAUUAGCUGUUUCUCAUUAGGCAAGUUAUAUAACCUUGCAGUGCCUCACUUUCCUCAUCUAUAAAAUGAGAUUAAAAUAGUCUUUUUAUUAAGAGAAUUAAAGUGAAUUGUGGCCAGGCACUGUGGCUCAUGCCUGUAAUCCCAGCGCUUUGGGAGGCUGAGGCAGACAGAUUGCUUGAGCUCAGAAGUUCGAGACUGGCCUGGGGAACAUGCAAAAACCCUGUCUGUAUUAAAAAUACAAAAAAAUUAGCUAGGUGUGGCGGCAUAUGCCUGUGGUCCCAGCUACUCAGGAGGCUGAAGUGGGAGGAUGGCUUGAGCCCGGGAGGCGGAGGUUGCAAUGAACUGAGAUCGCACCACUGUGUUCCAGACAGAGUGCGAUGCUGUCUCGAAAAAAGUAAAAUAAUAAAUAAAUAAUAAAUAAAAUAAAAUAAAGUGAAUUGUUACAUGUAAA